CGGCCGGCCUUCGCUUUGCGCACGCGCCUUUUGAGGUAACGGCCCAAAGAGGUGGAAGCGCUUUUCCCGCCCGGCCGCGGGGCGUGGCUCUGCGCGCAGCUUGAUGACGACUUUCGGCGCCGUGGCGGAAUGGCGGCUUCCAUCUCUGAGGCGAGCGACGCUAUGGAUCCCACAGGUGAGUGGCGCGGGAUGCGCGCCUGAGACGGUCCGGCGCCCUGGGGGCUUCCCCGAGCCCCUGCGGAGGCCAUCUCCGUUCCUCCGCGAGCCCCAGGACUCGGGCCGGCCAGCCGGCUCUGCCCAGGCAGGGCAGGCUGGGGAGUGGAGGGCCCCGGUUGAGUCUUCUGCCACCCCUCUGGGCCAUGCCUUUGUGCCACCUUCCCGCGCGGCUCGUACACUCUGUCCCGGUCCGUGGUUUGCUAAGAAGGCCAUUUUCAACUCUCCACUGGAGGCUGCUAUGGCGUUCCCUCACCUGCAGCAGCCCAGCUUUCUACUGGCUAGCCUGAAAGCUGACUCUAUAAAUAAGCCCUUUGCACAGCAGUGCCAAGACUUGGUUAAAGUCAUUGAGGACUUUCCAGCAAAGGAGCUGCACACCAUCUUCCCAUGGCUGGUAGAAAGCAUUUUUGGCAGCCUAGAUGGUGUCCUCGUUGGCUGGAACCUCCGCUGCUUACAGGGGCGCGUGAAUCCUGUGGAGUACAGCAUCGUGAUGGAAUUUCUCGACCCUGGUGGCCCAAUGAUGAAGUUGGUUUAUAAGCUUCAAGCUGAAGACUAUAAGUUCGACUUUCCUGUCUCCUACUUGCCUGGUCCUGUGAAGGCGUCCAUCCAGGAGUGCAUCCUCCCUGACAGUCCUCUGUACCACAACAAGGUCCAGUUCACCCCUACUGGGGGCCUUGGUCUGAACUUGGCCCUGAAUCCGUUCGAGUAUUACAUAUUCUUCUUUGCCUUGAGCCUCAUCACUCAGAAGCCACUUCCUGUGUCCCUCCACGUCCGUACUUCAGACUGUGCCUAUUUCAUCCUGGUGGACAGGUACCUGUCAUGGUUCCUGCCCACCGAAGGCAGUGUGCCCCCACCACUCUCCUCCAGCCCAGGGGGGACCAGCCCCUCACCACCUCCCAGGACACCAGCCAUACCCUUUGCUUCCUAUGGCCUCCACCACACUAGCCUCCUAAAGCGACACAUCUCUCAUCAGACGUCUGUGAAUGCAGACCCCGCCUCCCACGAGAUCUGGAGGUCAGAAACUCUGCUCCAGGUUUUUGUUGAAAUGUGGCUUCAUCACUAUUCCUUGGAGAUGUAUCAAAAAAUGCAGUCCCCUCAUGCCAAGCUGGAGGUUCUGCACUACCGACUCAGUGUCUCCAGCGCCCUCUACAGCCCCGCCCAACCCAGCCUCCAGGCCCUCCACGCCUACCAAGAGUCGUUCACGCCUACUGAGGAGCAUGUGUUGGUGGUGCGCCUGCUGCUGAAGCACCUGCACGCCUUUGCCAACAGCCUGAAGCCAGAGCAGGCCUCACCCUCCGCCCACUCCCACGCCACCAGCCCCCUGGAGGAGUUCAAACGAAUGGGGCUGAACCUCCCGGAGGUGCCCAGUGCUCUCCCCCGGCGGAGCCAACCCUCACUGAUGGGAGCCCUGGGGUCAUCUGUGAGCAGGGCCUCCUUACUGGGCAAGCAGCAGGUGACCCUCCCCAUCCCCUGCAGGGCUGCUGUCCCGAGGUUCGUCCAGCAGAAACUCUACCUCUUCUUGCAGCAUUGCUUUGGCCACUGGCCCCUGGACGCAUCGUUCAGAGCUGUCCUGGAGAUGUGGCUGAGCUACCUGCAGCCGUGGCGGUACGCGCCUGACAAGCAGGCUCCGGGCAGCGACUCCCAGCCCCGGUGUGUGUCGGAGAAAUGGGCACCCUUUGUCCAGGAGAACCUGCUGAUGUACACCAAGUUGUUUGUGGGCUUUCUGAACCGCGCGCUCCGCACAGACCUGGUCAGCCCCAAGCACGCGCUCAUGGUGUUCCGAGUGGCCAAAGUCUUUGCCCAGCCCAACCUGGCUGAGAUGAUUCAGAAAGGUGAGCAGCUAUUCCUGGAGCCAGAGCUGGUCAUCCCCCACCGCCAGCACCGACUCUUCACGGCCCCCACAUUCACUGGGAGCUUCCUGUCACCCUGGCCACCAGCGGUCACUGAUGCCUCCUUCAAGGUGAAGAGCCACGUCUACAGCCUGGAGGGCCAGGACUGCAAGUACACCCCGAUGUUUGGGCCCGAGGCCCGCACCCUGGUCCUGCGCCUCGCUCAGCUCAUCACACAGGCCAAACACACAGCCAAGUCCAUCUCCGACCAGUGUGCGGAGAGCCCGGCUGGCCACUCCUUCCUCUCAUGGCUGGGCUUUAGCUCCAUGGACACCAAUGGCUCCUACACAGCCAACGACCUGGACGAGAUGGGGCAAGACAGUGUCCGGAAGACAGAUGAAUACCUGGAGAAGGCCCUGGAGUACCUGCGCCAGAUAUUCCGGCUCAGCGAAGCGCAGCUCAGGCAGUUCACACUCGCCUUGGGCACCACCCAGGAUGAGAAUGGAAAAAAGCAACUCCCCGACUGCAUCGUGGGUGAGGACGGACUCAUCCUUACGCCCCUGGGGCGGUACCAGAUCAUCAAUGGGCUGCGAAGGUUUGAAAUUGAGUACCAGGGGGACCCGGAGCUGCAGCCCAUCCGGAGCUAUGAGAUCGCCAGCUUGGUCCGCACACUCUUUAGGCUGUCGUCUGCCAUCAACCACAGAUUUGCAGGACAGAUGGCGGCUCUGUGUUCCCGGGAUGACUUCCUCGGCAGCUUCUGUCGCUACCACCUCACAGAACCUGGGCUGGCCAGCAGGCACCUGCUGAGCCCUGUGGGGCGGAGGCAGGUGGCCGGCCACACCCGCGGCCCCAGGCUCAGCCUGCGCUUCCUGGGCAGUUACCGGACGCUGGUCUCGCUGCUGCUGGCCUUCUUCGUGGCCUCUCUGUUCUGCGUCGGGCCCCUCCCAUGCACGCUGCUGCUCACCCUGGGCUAUGUCCUCUACGCCUCUGCCAUGACACUGCUGACCGAGCGGGGGAAGCUGCACCAGCCCUGAAGGUGUCAGCUGCCUUCAGAGCAGGCUGGAGGGAUUUGCCACACAGCCCCACCCUUGGGCUGAGAGGACCUGGGAAGCCCCUCCAGGAGGGAACACGGUCAUCCUCGGGCUUCUGGAGCGGGGUUCCUGCAGCCGCAGAGGCAUCUGGAGGAAACGCAACCAAGAAAGGAAGGCAGGUGGGCCCCAGCAAAGGAGUAGCUGCCAGGGCUCAACAGCUACGCUCUGUGACAGCGCAGAGCUCAGCGGCGGCCUUUCCCUCCCUCCGCCAAGGACUCACGGCCAAGCCAGCUCUCGGGGCCUUUUUUCCACUGCCCAUUUGGCUACUCUGCUGCACCAAGCUUGGGAGCCAGCCUGCCAACAGCCACCUGGGCCUGGCCUCCCCACUGGCUGGCCUUGAGGUUGGCAGAGUGGGUUGUGGCGCUUCCUCUCUCUGUGUGGGACCAGGACAGUGGCUUAAGUCUCCACUCCAGGAAAGAAUCAAAGUUUCUAGAGUUGUGAGAAAACCAGAGAGUGGCUGUCCUGAUUCUUCACUGUGAGGGGCGUUCUUCAUGUUCUCCCAGCUGUUCCAAGACUGGGCCGUAGAAUUCCAUGUUUCAGGAGCCUAAGACCCUCCCAGAGCCCAGGGGCUUCACCGCAGACCCCAAGCCAUUGAGCACAUCACCCAAAGCAGUGGCCAACAUCGCGGACCCCUGUGCCUUGUCACAGAUGGGUGCUGGUCCUCAGGCGUUGGGGACACUGCUGGGUCGAUGGGGUCGGAUUCUGCCAGUUUCUGCUCUGCAGCCAAAGAUGGUCAGAAGCAUUGUCACUUCAGUAACAUCAAGUGCUCAAAGACAUGGCAACCGUUCAGUGGUACUUAAGUAUUCAAAAUAUACAACUACAGAUUCUCUGACAGAAACCAGCACGGGGUCUUCACCUUCAUUCACCCCACAGGCGACAUGCGAGGGAGAACAGCAUCUCAGUGGUGAUUUCCAAACCAAGCCUUUGUUUUCGGUGUGGGGUUUUGGGGGUUUGCUUUAAUGUUUUUGAAAUUGUAAAUGUUGGGCUUUGUAUUUUGAUGUAAACUGAGCAUAAUGGCAUUUUAGGGCCUGUGACCAAAAAUGAAGCUUGUAACGACCAUGGAUCUGAAUAAACAUGUCCUUGCUUCUGAGUCUUCUGGCACCUGG